GUUUGCAUGCGCUCAUCAAAAUCAAGUGUAGCUAUUUAGGGAAGCAAAGACCCUAGUCUAGGCCUGGAAAUGAGAUUCUCUUCUUUUUUGGCCUCCCCUUCUCUGGUUCUGAAAUCAAGUUUUCCUGGUCUCAUUACUAGGAAUUCUUCCUCUUCUUAUCACUACGCAGUACCCACAGCAAACCAGGAUAAUUGUAUAAGCCCCUUGGCUAUUUAAUGUUGCUCUGAACUCAACAGGUAUCUUGCAAGAAUAAACAAAUCCAUUGUGGACUGCAAGUCACUUGCUUUCAGGCUAGGGAGAAAAUGCAGCCUUAAGUCAAAAGGGCAUUUUCCCUCUCAGCUAGGAGAGCCCUGUCAAGAUAGGCUGCUGGUGUUCACAUCUCCCUCGCAGCGAACCCCAAAGCCGCCCUGGGAGGAGAACCCGGUGACCAAGAGGACCGACUCAGAGGCCGAGCGCGCUCAGGGCUCGGAAUGGGUCUGCAGGAAGUCGUCCCGAAAGAGCUGCCUGGACACGUGCGUGACACUCACCUGUUCACACUCUCCAGGCCAGGAGAGCUACGGUCCUCUGCAAGUUCGGAAUGGGUCCCCCAAGAUCGCGAAGCCCUCCCACACUGCGCAGCCCAGGCUUCAGGUUGCGUUUGCGAGUUGCUGGGCUGCGGUCGUGGGUGGGACUCGCCGCAGAAGCAAGUGCCAGUGGCCCGGCGGGGGUCUCCUCACUCGCGCUCGCUCCGACUAGCGGCGGAGGGACUGCGGCAGGACGCGAGCUGAGCCCGGCCAAGGCCGCUGCGCUCAGCGGCCAGGAUGCUGCAGUGCGGCGCUUCGGCGCCCCCUACUGGGGGCAGGGGCAGGCUCCUCCCGCCGCGCUGCCUCCCAGGCUUGCGAGCUUGGGUCUUUAACGUGCUGCACCCAAGACGGGCUUCCCUUUUUCACUGGUUAUUUCCAAGCCUCCAGGCUCCCACCGAAGGGCGGCUUUCCUCGGUCAAAACCUUGCCUAAGAAAGCAUCACUACGUGGUGUUUUCUAUUCCUUAUUUCAAAUGAUCCUCGCAAUAUCUCUUUGAAGUAUCUUUAAUUAUCUCCAUGAUACCCAAGAGGAAACUGAAGGAGAAGGUAACGCAAGGCUAGUAAAUGGCUGGAAUGAAAUCCAGACUGGAUUGGGAACUGAGAGAUGCUAGGAAAAACAAACAAGGAAUUCAAUUGAAAUUCUAUUCAUAUAUUUGAGAAAGUUCCAAAAGCUUCUCGUCCUCCUUACAGGAUCAGCAUUUAUAGGAUUUGCAUUGGAGUCAUACUCCAUUAUGCUCAGACCCUAACAAA